AGAACUGCGCUCUGAAGUUUCCAGAGAGCGAGGAGCUUUUGCGGCAGGCAGAGACAAUGGAAGAAAAUGAAAGCCAGAAAUGUGAGCCGUGCCUUCCUUACUCAGCAGACAGAAGACAGAUGCAGGAACAAGGCAAAGGCAAUCUGCAUGUAACAUCACCAGAAGAUGCAGAAUGCCGCAGAACCAAGGAACGCCUUUCUAAUGGAAACAGUCGUGGUUCAGUUUCCAAGUCUUCCCGCAAUAUCCCAAGGAGACACACCCUAGGGGGGCCCCGAAGUUCCAAGGAAAUACUGGGAAUGCAAACAUCUGAGAUGGAUCGGAAGAGAGAAGCGUUCCUAGAACAUCUGAAGCAGAAGUACCCCCACCACGCCUCUGCAAUCAUGGGUCACCAAGAGAGGCUGAGAGACCAGACAAGGAGCCCCAAACUGUCUCACAGUCCUCAACCACCCAGUCUGGGUGACCCGGUCGAGCAUUUAUCAGAGACGUCCGCUGAUUCUUUGGAAGCCAUGUCUGAGGGGGAUGCUCCAACCCCUUUUUCCAGAGGCAGCCGGACUCGUGCGAGCCUUCCUGUGGUGAGGUCAACCAACCAGACGAAAGAAAGAUCUCUGGGGGUUCUCUAUCUCCAGUAUGGAGAUGAAACCAAGCAGCUCAGGAUGCCGAAUGAAAUCACAAGUGCAGACACAAUCCGUGCUCUCUUCGUAAGUGCCUUUCCACAGCAGCUCACCAUGAAAAUGCUGGAAUCGCCCAGUGUCGCCAUUUACAUCAAAGAUGAAAGCAGAAAUGUCUAUUAUGAAUUAAAUGAUGUAAGGAACAUUCAAGACAGAUCACUCCUCAAAGUGUACAACAAGGAUCCUGCACAUGCGUUUAAUCACACACCAAAAACUAUGAAUGGAGACAUGAGGAUGCAGAGAGAACUUGUUUAUGCAAGAGGAGAUGGCCCUGGGGCCCCUCGCCCCGGAUCUACUGCUCAUCCACCCCAUGCGAUUCCAAAUUCCCCACCGUCUACUCCAGUGCCCCAUUCCAUGCCCCCCUCCCCGUCCAGAAUUCCUUAUGGGGGCACCCGCUCCAUGGUUGUUCCUGGCAAUGCCACCAUCCCCAGGGACAGAAUCUCCAGCCUGCCAGUCUCCAGACCCAUCUCUCCAAGCCCAAGCGCCAUUUUAGAAAGAAGAGAUGUCAAGCCUGAUGAAGACAUGAGUGGCAAAAACAUUGCAAUGUACAGAAAUGAGGGUUUCUAUGCUGAUCCUUACCUUUAUCACGAGGGACGGAUGAGCAUAGCCUCAUCCCAUGGUGGACACCCACUGGAUGUCCCCGACCACAUCAUUGCAUAUCACCGCACCGCCAUCCGGUCAGCGAGUGCUUAUUGUAACCCCUCAAUGCAAGCGGAAAUGCAUAUGGAACAAUCACUGUACAGACAGAAAUCAAGGAAAUAUCCGGAUAGCCAUUUGCCUACACUGGGCUCCAAAACACCCCCUGCCUCUCCUCACAGAGUCAGUGACCUGAGGAUGAUAGACAUGCACGCUCACUAUAAUGCCCACGGCCCCCCUCACACCAUGCAGCCAGACCGGGCCUCUCCGAGCCGCCAGGCCUUUAAAAAGGAGCCAGGCACCUUGGUGUAUAUAGAAAAGCCACGGAGCGCUGCAGGAUUAUCCAGCCUUGUAGACCUCGGCCCUCCUCUAAUGGAGAAGCAAGUUUUUGCCUACAGCACGGCGACAAUACCCAAAGACAGAGAGACCAGAGAGAGGAUGCAAGCCAUGGAGAAACAGAUUGCCAGUUUAACUGGCCUUGUUCAGUCUGCGCUUUUUAAAGGGCCCAUUACAAGUUAUAGCAAAGAUGCGUCUAGCGAGAAAAUGAUGAAAACCACAGCCAACAGGAACCACACAGAUAGUGCAGGAACGCCCCAUGUGUCUGGUGGGAAGAUGCUCAGUGCUCUGGAGUCCACGGUGCCUCCCAGCCAGCCUCCACCUGUGGGCACCUCAGCCAUCCACAUGAGCCUGCUUGAGAUGAGGCGGAGCGUGGCGGAACUCAGGCUCCAGCUCCAGCAGAUGCGGCAGCUCCAGCUGCAGAACCAGGAGUUGCUGAGGGCAAUGAUGAAGAAGGCCGAGCUGGAAAUCAGUGGCAAAGUGAUGGAAACAAUGAAGAGACUGGAGGAUCCCGUGCAGCGACAGCGCGUCCUAGUGGAGCAAGAGAGACAAAAAUAUCUUCAUGAGGAAGAGAAGAUCGUCAAGAAGUUGUGCGAGUUGGAAGACUUUGUUGAAGACUUGAAGAAGGACUCCACGGCAGCCAGCCGAUUGGUUACUCUGAAAGACGUGGAAGACGGGGCUUUCCUCCUGCGUCAAGUGGGAGAGGCUGUAGCUACCCUGAAAGGAGAAUUUCCAACCUUACAAAACAAGAUGCGAGCCAUCCUGCGCAUAGAAGUGGAGGCCGUGCGGUUUCUGAAGGAGGAGCCACACAAGCUGGACAGUCUCCUGAAGCGUGUGCGCAGCAUGACAGACGUCCUGACCAUGCUGCGGAGACAUGUCACUGAUGGGCUCCUGAAAGGCACGGACGCAGCCCAAGCCGCACAGUACAUGGCUAUGGAAAAGGCCACAGCCGCAGAAGUCCUGAAGAGUCAGGAGGAGGCAGCCCACACCUCCGGCCAGCCCUUCCACAGCACAGGUGCCCCUGGCGAUGCGAAGUCGGAAGUGGUGCCUUUGUCCGGCAUGAUGGUUCGCCACGCGCAGAGCUCCCCUGUGGUCAUCCAGCCCUCCCAGCACUCCGUGGCCCUGCUGAACCCUGCUCAGAACUUGCCUCACGUGGCCAGCUCCCCAGCCGUCCCCCAGGAAGCAACCUCCACUCUGCAGAUGUCGCAGGCUCCGCAGUCCCCACAGAUACCCAUGAAUGGGUCUGCCAUGCAGAGCUUGUUCAUUGAAGAAAUCCACAGUGUGAGUGCCAAGAACAGGGCAGUGUCUAUCGAGAAAGCAGAAAAGAAAUGGGAGGAAAAAAGGCAAAAUCUGGAUCACUAUAAUGGGAAAGAGUUUGAGAAGCUCCUAGAAGAAGCUCAGGCCAAUAUCAUGAAGUCAAUACCAAAUCUGGAGAUGCCGCCAGCCACAGGCCCACUGCCAAGGGGAGAUGCCCCAGUGGACAAGGUGGAACUUUCAGAUUCUCCAAAUUCGGAACAGGACUUGGAAAAGCUGGGGGGAAAGUCGCCCCCUCCUCCUCCGCCACCUCCUCGUCGAAGCUACCUGCCAGGAUCGGGACUCACCACCACGAGGUCAGGCGAUGUGGUCUACACCGGCAGAAAGGAGAACAUCACCGCUAAGGCAAGCAGUGAAGAUGCUGGACCAAGCCCACAGACCAGAGCUACAAAAUAUCCAGCAGAGGAGCCUGCUUCAGCCUGGACCCCAUCCCCACCGCCUGUCACCACCUCCUCCUCAAAGGAUGAGGAGGAAGAAGAAGAAGAAGGAGACAAAAUAAUGGCAGAACUCCAGAAUUUGGAAUUUUUCCAUGAAGAUGUACGGAAAUCUGAUGUUGAAUAUGAAAAUGGCCCCCAAAUGGAAUUCCAAAAGGUUACCACAGGGGCUGUAAGACCUAGUGACCCUCCUAAGUGGGAAAGAGGAAUGGAGAAUAGUAUUUCUGAUGCAUCAAGAACAUCAGAAUAUAAAACUGAGAUCAUAAUGAAGGAAAAUUCCAUAUCCAAUAUGAGUUUACUCAGAGACAGUAGAAACUAUUCCCAGGAAACUGUGCCUAAGGCCAGUUUCGGUUUCUCUGGCAUUAGUCCAUUAGAAGAUGAAAUAAACAAAGGGUCUAAAAUCUCAGGCCUGCAAUACUCUAUACCUGACACCGAGAACCAGACGCUGAAUUACGGAAAGACAAAGGAGAUGGAAAAGCAAAAUACGGAUAAGUGUCACGUUUCCUCUCACACUAGACUAACAGAAUCAAGCGUGCAUGAUUUUAAAACAGAAGAUCAAGAGGUUAUCACGACAGAUUUUGGCCAAGUUGUUCUAAGACCCAAGGAGGCAAGGCAUGCUAACGUGAACCCUAAUGAGGAUGGAGAAUCAAGUUCAAGUUCUCCCACUGAAGAAAAUGCAGCCACUGACAAUAUUGCCUUCAUGAUUACCGAAACCACUGUCCAGGUUCUUUCCAGUGGGGAGGUGCAUGAUAUUGUUAGCCAAAAGGGAGAAGACAUACAGACGGUUAAUAUCGAUGCCAGAAAAGAGAUGACCCCCCGACAAGAAGGGACUGACAAUGAGGAUCCAGUCGUGUGCCUGGACAAGAAACCAGUGAUCAUCAUUUUCGAUGAGCCCAUGGACAUCCGGUCUGCCUAUAAGAGACUUUCAACUAUCUUUGAGGAAUGUGAUGAGGAAUUAGAGAGAAUGAUGAUGGAGGAAAAGAUAGAGGAGGAGGAAGAGGAGGAAAAUGGGGAUUCUGUAGUCCAGAAUAAUAACACUUCCCAGAUGUCUCAUAAGAAGGUGGCCCCAGGCAAUCUUAGAACCGGACAACAGGUGGAAACAAAGUCACAGCCACACUCCCUGGCCACAGAGACCAGAAACCCAGGAGGACAGGAAAUGAACAGAACGGAGCUGAACAAGUUCAGCCACGUGGAUUCUCCAAAUUCGGAAUGCAAGGGUGAGGACGCGACCGAUGACCAGUUUGAAAGCCCCAAGAAAAAGUUUAAAUUCAAAUUCCCUAAGAAGCAACUCGCCGCUCUCACUCAAGCCAUUCGCACCGGAACUAAAACAGGGAAGAAGACUUUGCAAGUGGUAGUCUAUGAAGAAGAGGAAGAGGAUGGCACCCUGAAACAGCACAAAGAAGCCAAGCGCUUCGAAAUCGCUAGGUCUCAACCUGAAGACACCCCUGAAAACACAGUGAGGAGGCAAGAGCAGCCCAGCAUCGAGAGUACAUCUCCGAUUUCAAGAACUGAUGAAAUUAGAAAAAACACCUACAGAACAUUGGAUAGCCUGGAGCAGACCAUUAAACAGCUCGAAAAUACAAUCAGUGAAAUGAGUCCCAAAGCCCUAGUUGAUACCUCAUGUUCUUCCAACAGAGAUUCUGUUGCAAGUUCAUCCCACAUAGCCCAAGAGGCCUCUCCCCGACCCUUGCUAGUUCCGGAUGAAGGUCCCACUGCCCUAGAGCCCCCUACGUCGAUACCUUCAGCUUCACGUAAGGGCUCCAGCGGGGCCCCACAGACGAGCAGGAUGCCUGUCCCCAUGAGUGCCAAGAACAGACCCGGAACCCUGGACAAACCCGGCAAGCAGUCCAAACUGCAGGAUCCCCGCCAAUAUCGUCAGGUAGUUUUACCUUAAACCCACUUUUGGAUGGACGCUAUUUCAGUUAAGCAAGUCACUGACUUAGUUUAUACCAAAUAUUGUGCUUUCUUUGUAAGAUAACGGUUUACAUAGACAUCCUGGAUCUGGGGGCAUGAAGAAAGUCUAAAUAAACCUUUGUUACACUUUUUUACCACGCUUUUGCAUGCUUGCAAUAAAACAUCUUUUACUUUGUGACUCCAAACUCCAAAUUUUAACUGUUAACACACGGUGCCAGACCAGGUGGCUUUUCUUUGGUGAAUGUAGUGUUUCAUCUGAACACCUCGGGAAGCAGAGACAAACCAACCUGUGGUUGAACUGCCCUUAACGUCACCACUACUAACGUCUAUGUUGACUGUAUUGUGUUAGAAGCACAUUAACACUCCGUCACAAUGCCCGACCCCCACCCCAGUAAUUAUCCAGACGCAUGGCCCACCUGGCACACAGGAAAUGGUAGAGCUGGAAUGAUGGGACUCCUCUCACAAAUGUAUUCUUCCUUUCCUCCUUUCCCGUCCAUCCUUUGCUAUGUACAUGGGGGGUUUCUACCAGGUCCAGUAGAGCACAACAAGACUUAGCUCAGGCCUUGAACUGUGUUUGGUUGGUUUUCUUUGAUUGAAUUAUUCUCAGAAGGGCUGUGUUGCCAGGCCCUGUGGGUUGAUCAUGUGACCGCCUUUCUGACAAAAUGUCUCCCGCCAUCUUUAUUUGCAGGCUAAUGGAAGUGCUAAGAAAUCUGGUGGGGACUUUAAGCCUACUUCCCCCUCCUUACCUGCUUCUAAGAUUCCAGCCCUUUCUCCCAGCUCUGGGAAAAGCAGUUCUCUGCCCUCUUCUAGUGGUGACAGCUCUAACCUCCCUAAUCCACCUGCUACUAAACCAUCGAUUGCUUCUAACCCUCUCAGCCCCCAAACAGGACCACCUGCUCACUCUGCCUCCCUCAUCCCUUCUGUCUCUAAUGGCUCUUUGAAGUUUCAGAGCCUCACUCAUACAGGUAAAGGUCACCAUCUUUCAUUCUCACCGCAGAGUCAAAAUGGCCGAGCACCCCCUCCUUUGUCAUUUUCCUCCUCCCCUCCUUCUCCUGCCUCCUCCGUCUCACUGAAUCAAGGUGCCAAGGGCACCAGGACCAUCCAUACUCCCAGCCUCACCAGCUACAAGGCACAGAAUGGAAGUUCAAGCAAAGCCACCCCAUCCACAGCAAAAGAAACCUCUUAAAGGUCAAAUCCUAUUAGGCACAAGUCGGAGUUACAUUUAAAAAAAAUUAACAGUCUACAACAACUGUUUUCACAAGAGAAUGUAACAUAUUGCUGUAUCGUUUGAGGCUUAAUGCUAAAUAUGUGCUAAAUACUGGAUUAAUAGAUUUCAGUAAAGCUCGUUCGUUUUGUUUGGUUUUCUUUUUACCUAGUUGCUAUAGUGUCUACAGUCUAUACUCAAUACCUAUAAAAUGCAGUAAGCAUGUGUUACAGAAAGAGGUUCUGGUGGGAGAGAAAGGUGCGUGUGAGACAGGAGAAUUGUCUUAAGCAUAUAAAACAUGUAUGAUUCCAGAAUUUUAGUAUGUUUUGUAUAAAACUAUUUUUCAUUACGGAGACUAGAAGUGAACAGAGAAUUACACAAGUGUGACUAUACAAAUUGUAAAACAGAUACUAUAAUAUUUCCUUUUAUUUUAGUGUUAUUUAGCUUUAUUACAGAUUUCUAUUUUUGUCAAAACUUCAUGGUUCCUUUCAAGAUCUUUUUUGCCAAAACAUUUUGAUACUAUAGCAUUGUACAUUUGAAAGUAGUGUUCUAGACUAUAAAACCAAUGAACUUCUACAUGAGCCCUACAGACAGGCAUGUGUAGAAGGCAAUUUAUCAAACCUAUUGCACUGCCAUGAAAAGUGUGUAUAAUAAUUUGCUAGCCCAAGCAAGCUAGUUUUCUUUGCUUGCUUCUUUUCUUUCUUUUUUCCUUCCUUUUUUUUUUUUUUUUCUUUUUUAACAUGUUGAGAUUCUCUAGUUGUUUUCUUUGGCGUAUCUAACCCCUUCUUUUGUUUUCUGAGACCUGGUAACCCACGCUCUUGCAUUGUGGAUUUUAAAAUGUAUACUCUGUACGGUUCUGUAAACCGAAAAACUUUUGUAAAUAUAUAAAUAUACAUAGACAUAAAAAUACUGUAUGUGACAGCACAUAGAGUAGUUUUCCCACACCAAAGUUAAUUUUUAUGCAUGCUUUAAAAGUAUAUAUCGGGACCGGCAGAAAUGGAAGUAUCCAUACAUUUUUAAAAAGCAACAAGUUUGCACAGCUAGAGUGUUUUUGUAAAUAAAUGUAUUUGUAUAACACAGUCAUGUAAUAUACAGAACUAUAAGCAGAGACUUUGCAAAACUAAAUAAAGGGCUGCAUGCUUAUUAUUUUUUGUACCUUGUCACUAUAACUACUUCCUAGUCAAAGAACGAAAUGUAACUGUUACCGAGUUAAAUGUUUUUCCGCUUUGAGGGAUGUAACCACAUCCACUCAGAGGACACUACUUUUCUGAAAGCUCUGGGGUGACUAAUGAUGAGUUCCUAAUAAAUUAAUUGCAAGUGUGGUGCCUUGGAUGUGGCCUGUUGGCUCGCUUUCUUCUCUGUGGCUUAUCAAGGUGUAGAUGACAGAAAGCAAACCUGGAUACAGAGUUUCCACCCUCAGUUCCUGGAGGGGCUCUUAUUAUUUUCUCUCUUUUUAAAAAACUUCCAGUAGAAGUAAAGUGGAAAUAAAAUGUCUUUAUCA